GCACUCGGCGGCGGGCGGGCGCGCGGCUGCAGCUGGAGCUCCAGCGCCCGGAGUUGGAGUUGCCGGGAGUUUCCCCCCAACCCCUCCCUUUUCGCGCGCGGCAGCAGGAGCCGGCGCGGGAGCCGCGAGCGGCGGCGAGCCAGCACCCGGGCCGGCUAAGCCUUGUCCGGAGCCCGGAGCCCCGCGCGGGGCAGCCCCCCGGGGAGGAGCCUCGUGCUCUGGGACGCGUGCCGCGCACUGGCACGGCAGGGGCGCGAGCCAGGCUGCACGGUAGGACCGGGGCGAGGGGAGCCAGGCGGUCAGGGCGGAGGCCAAGCCCGGGAGAUGCGGUUGCAGCCGCCACGGCUGUUGGGGCGCCUGGCGCUCCGUCCGAGGCGGGUGGCUGUGAGGCCAGGGGAGUAGGCAGGCUCCCAGAGAGAUUCUUCCAAGUUGGCGGGUGGCGGGAGAGGGGGCCGCGCGCCCCGGCGCAGCUGCUUUGUGCGCGCAGAGAGGGACUCGUGUCCCUGGUUCUCUCCAACCCUGGGACCCGUUGUGCGGGCAGUAUUGGGCAAGCCGCAGAACGGAGCGAUUUCCUCCGAGAAAGUUGAGGAUGGAGCCUUUUUUUCCGCACCGUCCCCGCGAUGGCAUGGGCCCCGAGAAUGCUGCCCCGAGGCUCCCAGUGUGGGGGAGCUCGGGGUCGCUGCGCCUCUAGCUUGAGCGCAGAAAUCCGCGAAUCACUCCGAUCUUCGCGAACUCUGGCAUCUUCUAGGAAAAUCAUUACUGCCAAAACUGAGGCGAGCUUUUCUGGCGGGCACGGCACCCUGCCCCCAGGGCGCUGGCCCUGGGCGAUGCCCCCUUUCCGAUCUCAGGCUUGGUCAAGGGCGCCAGGUUCCGAAUUCGCGCUUGCCGUGCACGCCGGCAUCGAGCCUCACCAACACCGCCGGGCAACGUGGCUGGAGUAGGCUAGAGUAGUGCAGUGGCGUGAUCUCAGCUCACUCCAGCCUCUGCCUCCCGGGCUCAAGUGACCCACCUGCCUCAGCCUCCCAAGUAGCUGGGACAACAGAUGUGAGCCACCACACCCAGAUUCACUGCGUGCUGUCCUCACUUGUUCUACAAUGAGUGCCAAAUCUGCUAUCAGCAAGGAAAUUUUUGCACCUCUUGAUGAAAGGAUGCUGGGAGCUGUCCAAGUCAAGAGGAGGACAAAGAAAAAGAUUCCUUUCUUGGCAACUGGAGGUCAAGGCGAAUAUUUAACUUAUAUCUGCCUGUCAGUGACAAACAAGAAACCCACACAGGCGUCCAUCACAAAGGUCAAACAGUUUGAAGGCUCCACAUCAUUUGUUCGGAGAUCACAGUGGAUGCUCGAGCAGCUUCGCCAGGUUAAUGGUAUCGAUCCUAAUGGGGAUUCGGCAGAGUUUGAUUUGUUGUUUGAAAAUGCUUUUGACCAGUGGGUAGCCAGCACAGCGUCAGAAAAAUGCACCUUCUUCCAGAUCCUCCACCAUACCUGCCAGAGGUACCUCACGGACAGGAAGCCAGAGUUUAUUAACUGCCAAUCCAAAAUUAUGGGAGGAAACAGCAUCCUCCAUUCAGCUGCUGACAGCGUGACCAGCGCAGUGCAGAAGGCAAGCCAGGCCUUGAAUGAGCGUGGAGAGCGAUUAGGCCGAGCAGAGGAGAAGACAGAAGACCUGAAGAACAGCGCCCAGCAGUUUGCAGAAACUGCGCACAAGCUUGCCAUGAAGCACAAAUGUUGAGAAACUGCCUAUCCUGGUGACUCUUCUUAAGAGAAACUGAAGAGUUUGUUCAGCAGUUUUUACAAGAAUUCGGGACCUCCGCUUGCUUCUUUUUUUCCAAUAUUUGGACACUUAGAGUGGUUUUUGUUUUUUCUUUUCAGAUGUUAAUGUGAAAGAAAGGGUGUUGCAUUUUUACAUUUCCCUAAUGAUCUUGCUAAUAAAUGCUACAAUAGCAUCAGCUUCAUUUUGGGUUUUUGCCUCCUCCCACUGUGUGUAUGUGUGUAUAUGUAUGUUUUGAAUAUGUUUUCUUUAUUAAAAAAUAUUUUUUGUAGUUUGAAUAUGAAAUUUGGACCAAAUGAUAAACUGCGCUGAGUCUAAACUGGCAACAUGUAUUUUUUUCUCUGAUAUUAAGCAGGAAGGCAUUUUAAUGUGGUGACAUCAGAUGUUAUUUUUCCUAGAUGAAAAUAAAAGUCAAGCAGUGAUUAGUUUCACUCACUGUCCUAGCUACACUUAAUUUGAAGAUUAAAAUUCUACAUUGUGGAAAACAAUUGAAUUUAUUGGGAAAAACAGCAGUCUUAGAUUUUGCUCCUUGCAUAGUAAUCUUUUGCAUGAACCAUCACCAGCGUUCAAAAAAAAAAAAAAAUCAGAAUCGCAGAUAGAAAUCUCUUUCCUGAGUUACAGUUUAAAUACUCUUGCUACUUGUAUCCAGGGUGUUUACUUGGAAUUAUCAUAUGAAGGGUAAAAAUUUGAGAGUAAAGCCCUAAAGAAAAGCCUACCUAAAACCCUCUGUGUACUCACAGAUGUUUCUCUUGUCACUGUCAUAGUGAUGGUCGCUGGUAUGGAAAAGUGCUUAUAUUUUUAUCAAAAAAUUGAUUUGUCCAGGUAAAGGUCUGUGUCAAUGAUAAUGUGAACAAGUAGUACAUUUAAAAUGUUUGUCUUGUCUUUUUACAGUCAUGCCUAUUUUAGAGACACCUUCAUAAUGUCCUUGGGAGAGGGCCUUUAGUUUCUUGGUAUCUGGAUUUUGGAGGUUUUGAUGUUGUUUUUGCUAUCUAUUUAUUUAAUGUAAUUUAAUAUGUGAGUUUCUUGACAAAUUGCAUUUCAUGGCAAUUGCACCUUGCCUGGUCUGAUAUAAAACACCACAAUCACAAACCUUUACAUUGCAGUCAGUUUCAAUACAGUUGGUCACACACCUCGUGAUUUUCUAUUACUCAAGAUAAUAAGGGGCUUAGGGUCUAGAAGUUCUGUUUCCUAGAGGGUUAAAAUGCUAAACAUAAAAAAAGCUGUGCUUUUUUUGUGAAACUAGGAGACAAGCUGCACAUCUCAGACACAUUGUAAGCCUACCACUGCAGCGCAUUGAUUUUUAAGCUGCCUGAAUCUUCAGGACCCCUAUCUAUUCCAUCCUAUCCAUUUUGCUGAUUGAGUCGAUAUGUAUUGCAGCCUCUUACAUAGGAGCAUAAGAUGACUUUUGGAUUGUUAAUACUGAUUUAAAUAGCUGAAGUUCUCCUAAUAAAGCAUUCCCAAGGAGAGAGAAAGUUUGUCUACUGGGGGUAAAAAUAUCAGAUGGUGCACAUUAAAAGGGAGAUGAGAUUUGUCGGAGACAGAUUUCAGAAUCCUUUUAGAUGAUCCAAUUCAAGAAAACCCUCUAUAAAAUUUAAUAAACUGUAUAAGUUAACUAUAAUAUUUUAUACUUUCUUUUUGGUGUCUUAAAAAUUUAAAGAAGCGAGGAACAUGCCAUUUGGUGAGUACCGUUGGAAGCUAUUUUAAUUUCUAGGAAAAGCCCCAAAUAUCACUCCAAAUAGAUUUUGUUUGCAGAUCUCAGUUCAGAAUGCACACACACACACACACACACACACACACACACACAGAGAUGUAUUUAUCUUUCCAAAUUGGAUUCUGGUUUCAGAGAUAGAGAGUUGGUAUAAAUAAUUGAAAGGAUAAAUCUAAAACCCCCUGACAGUCCGCCAAAUUCAAGAACAGAAGUGGUUGCCAACUCUCUAACAACAAUGUUUGGGAAGCUGAUUCCAAAGUAGCUGAGGAUGAGGUCAUAAGCAUACUGUGAAACCCAAGAUUCUUCUUCCCUGGUAGAAUUACAAUAGUUACUCUUGAUAAAUAUAAGUAUUCCAUGUCUUGCCCUCUUUCCUCACUCUCUGCUUAUCCUUUUAGACCUAAGUUUCAUUGGAAAUAGCCUGAAUUAGAAGAAAGCCCAUCCGAAUCUUUAUUAGCCCCCUCUAAUGAUUAGUUUCCAGGCUGCGUUCAUACCUUUGACCUCUCAGUGUCAAAGUCCUACCUAGGCCUCCCCACAACAGAGAGGGCCGUAACAGCAAUCCCUGCCCCUCCUUUACCUCCCAGCCUCUUGCAGAGGAGCCCAGUGAUAACACAUGUGAAGUUCUUUGCUGUCCUCUUGUAGAAGGUGCUGCAGUGCAAAGUAUUAAUACGGUCUUAGACAAAAUAACUGUCAUGAUUUGGGACCAGUUUGGUUGAGCUUGUCAGAAGACAUUUCAUUUGUUUCAUUUCUGCACUUCUCUAUGAAUUUUGGGAUACUAUAUUUCUGUGAAGGACUUAUUGUAUAGACAACUCAAAAAGGAAAGAAACUUUCCAGUAUUACCACUUCUUCCUGGAAUAUAGCUGUAGUAUUUCUCACUAGUAUUAUUAGAUACCUGUGUACAGAAAGUAUGCAGUUAUUCAGGUUAAUGUUUCAUAUUAAAGAAUGUAUUUGUAAAAUGUAACAUGAUCAGUAGUUACCUUUUUUCAAGCUCUGAAGAAGUUCAGAUUACGUGUUAGACUUAAGUUACAGUGAAAACUGUUUUAAUACUACUUUUGUGGCUAGCAAAGGUUGUGCAUCUAUUUAAAAUUAUUUACAGGAUGCUCUAAAUAAGGGGCAUUAAAGAUAGGUUUAGCUCUUAAUUUUAGAAAUUGUGACACUACUGAUGUCUGUCAUACAGUUAUUCUUCAGAAGUUCUCUGAGAUGUCAAAUAUAAUUUUUGUUUAAUUCAGAGAUAAGUAACACCUGCUCUAUUGAUUCACUAUUACAACAAACCCUAAUUUUGUCAUUAAAUAUUUUAACUCUGUGAUGAAAUUUGUUUCUUGCAGUUAUUUAUGAACUCUAUAAAACACUACCAAAUAAGUACAUGUCACCACAUUUUUUAUGCUAAUAGGAAAAUCUUAUGUGCCUAAGGGGAAACCUCAGAACUAGUAUUAGCAUGAUGAUAAAAUGUCAUUACAUAUGUUCUAAUGGAAAAGCUUGGAAUGUAAUAAAGACUAAAGAGCUAACCUUAA